ACUUGCGACGCAGGCGCAGAGGCUGGGCGUGCAGCCGCCGCCGCAGAGCCGGAGCGGGGGCCGCCGGCGCCGUUUGGCUGCCAUAGGCGUGGUAGGAGUGGGACUUGUGAACCAAGGGAUGGCCCUACCUGACGUCUGGAAUACUCUGGAAGGGGCCUUGUGUGACGUGGGCUUGGAAAAGUGUAGGCUGAUGGGCAUUGUCUCCUGGUAACUUCAGGGAAUGUCUUGAUUGUCCCAGCAUCCCUCUCUACCUGCCAACAUCCUGUAUUAGAGAACUUGUGGCCGGAGGUGUGGCUGUGGAGAGCUGGCCGGGGAGGGACGCUGCUCAGCUGCUGCUCUGCUCCUGUCUCCUGUCCCCUCCCCCGGUCAUGACAGAGACCCGUGAGCCAGCUGAGACUGGGGGCUACGCCAGCUUGGAAGAAGAUGAUGAAGACCUUUCCCCAGGCCCCGAGCAUUCCUCUGAUUCAGAAUACACUCUCUCAGAGCCGGACUCCGAAGAGGAAGAAGAUGAGGAGGAGGAGGAAGAGGAGACCACUGACGAUCCUGAAUAUGAUCCUGGCUACAAGGUGAAGCAGCGCCUUGGCGGGGGCCGUGGUGGCCCAUCCCGCCGGGCCCCCCGUGCAGCCCAGCCCCCGGCCCAGCCUUGCCAGCUCUGUGGCCGCUCACCCCUUGGGGAGGCCCCACCGGGAACCCCACCCUGCCGGCUCUGCUGCCCUGCUACAGCCCCCCAGGAAGCACCAGCCCCUGAAGGCAGGGCCCUCGGGGAGGAAGAGGAGGAACCACCUCGGGCUGGGGAGGGCCGACCAGCUGGGCGGGAGGAGGAGGAGGAAGAGGAGGAGGAGGGAACCUACCACUGUACGGAAUGUGAGGAUUCCUUCGACAACCUGGGGGAGCUGCACGGGCACUUCAUGCUGCAUGCCCGGGGUGAGGUGUAGGCAGAGCCCCCAUACGGGGAGCUUGGCAGAAGGGGUGGGGUGGGAGGAGGGGGCUGAGGAAAUUGGGGUUGUGACAGUGGUCAUGGGGGAUGGGGUACUGCCGGUCUGUGUUGUCUUAGAAGUAGAUGUGUGAUGGCCAGAAUAAAAGCCAAAAUCUGUAUCUGUGUGUGUUGGUUCAGAGUGUGUGUGUGUGUGUGUGUAUUCCCGCCCGUGUGUGUGUUUGUGUGUGUGUGUGUGUGUGUGUAUUCCCCCUGGGCUCCUUCUUGGGGAACCUUGGGGUCUUUUGGGAAAGAUAACAUUUACUGCGUGCUUGUAUUCGAUGAGGUUUCCAUGUAUUUACUUACAGACCCCAUAAUGUAAAGGCUCUAAUAAUAGAAUUUUGUUUCUCACUCA